ACUCGACCCAAAGGUGCAGGCGCGCGAGCACAACCCAUGGCUGCGCUGGGCUGCGCGAGGCUGAGGUGGGCGCUGCGAGGGGCCGGCCGUGGCCUCUGCCCCCACGGGGCCAGAGCCAAGGCCGCGAUCCCUGCCGCCCUCCCCUCGGACAAGGCCACCGGAGCUCCCGGAGCCGGGCCUGGUGUCCGGCGGCGGCAACGGAGCUUAGAGGAGAUUCCACGUCUAGGACAGCUGCGCUUCUUCUUUCAGCUGUUCGUUCAAGGCUAUGCCCUGCAACUGCACCAGUUACAGGUGCUUUACAAGGCCAAGUACGGUCCAAUGUGGAUGUCCUACUUAGGGCCUCAGAUGCACGUGAACCUGGCCAGUGCCCCGCUCUUGGAGCAAGUGAUGCGGCAAGAGGGCAAGUACCCAGUACGGAACGACAUGGAGCUAUGGAAGGAGCACCGGGACCAGCACGACCUGACCUAUGGGCCGUUCACCACGGAAGGACACCACUGGUACCAGCUGCGCCAGGCUCUGAACCAGCGGUUGCUGAAGCCAGCGGAAGCAGCGCUCUAUACGGAUGCUUUCAAUGAGGUGAUUGAUGACUUUAUGACUCGACUGGACCAGCUGCGGGCAGAGAGUGCUUCGGGGAACCAGGUGUCGGACAUGGCUCAACUCUUCUACUACUUUGCCUUGGAAGCUAUUUGCUACAUCCUGUUCGAGAAACGCAUUGGCUGCCUGCAGCGAUCCAUCCCCGAGGACACCGUGACCUUCGUCAGAUCCAUCGGGUUAAUGUUCCAGAACUCACUCUAUGCCACCUUCCUCCCCAAGUGGACUCGCCCCGUGCUGCCUUUCUGGAAGCGAUACCUGGAUGGUUGGAAUGCCAUCUUUUCCUUUGGGAAGAAGCUGAUUGAUGAGAAGCUCGAAGAUAUGGAGGCCCAACUGCAGGCAGCAGGGCCAGAUGGCAUCCAGGUGUCUGGCUACCUGCACUUCUUACUGGCCAGUGGACAGCUCAGUCCUCGGGAGGCCAUGGGCAGCCUGCCUGAGCUGCUCAUGGCUGGAGUGGACACGACAUCCAACACGCUGACAUGGGCCCUGUACCACCUCUCAAAGGACCCUGAGAUCCAGGAGGCCUUGCACGAGGAAGUGGUGGGUGUGGUGCCAGCCGGGCAAGUGCCCCAGCACAAGGACUUUGCCCACAUGCCGUUGCUCAAAGCUGUGCUUAAGGAGACUCUGCGUCUCUACCCUGUGGUCCCCACAAACUCCCGGAUCAUAGAAAAGGAAAUUGAAGUUGAUGGCUUCCUCUUCCCCAAGAACACCCAGUUUGUGUUCUGCCACUAUGUGGUGUCCCGGGACCCCACUGCCUUCUCUGAGCCUGAAAGCUUCCAGCCCCACCGCUGGCUGAGAAACAGCCAGCCUGCUACCCCCAGGAUCCAGCACCCAUUUGGCUCUGUGCCCUUUGGCUAUGGGGUCCGGGCCUGCCUGGGCCGCAGGAUUGCAGAGCUGGAGAUGCAGCUACUCCUCGCAAGGCUGAUCCAGAAGUACAAGGUGGUCCUGGCCCCGGAGACGGGGGAGUUGAAGAGUGUGGCCCGCAUUGUCCUGGUUCCCAAUAAGAAAGUGGGCCUGCAGUUCCUGCAGAGACAGUGCUGAGCUGAGUCUCCGCCUUGCUGGGGCUUGUCCUAGAGGCUCCAGCUCUGGCACAGUGGUUCCUGGCUGCUGCCAUGUCUCAGAUGAGGAGGGAGAGAAGGAGGCCGCCAGACUCGAGAGGUGGGAGGAACUCCUUGCACACACCCUGAGCUUUUGCCACUUCUAUCAUUUUUGAGCAACUCCCUCUCAGCUAAAAGGCCACCCCUUUAUCGCAUUGCUGUCCUUGGGUAGAAUAUAAAAUAAAGGGACUUUUAUUUCUUAUUGGA